GCAUUUCCCCUUUUGAGACAGGGUCUCACUCUGUCACUGAGGCUGGAAUGCUAAGGGGUGAUCAUAGCUCCCUGCAGCCUCCGCCUCCCAGGCCGAAGUAUUCCUCCCACCUCAGCCUCCUGAGUAGCUGGGACUAGAGAUGUGAGCUGCCAUGCCUGGCUAAUUUUUUGCUUUUUUUAUACAGACAAGGUCUUGCUAUGUGGCCCAGGGUAAUCUGAAGCUCCUGGCCUCUAGCCUUCACCCACCUCAGCCUCCUGAAGUGCUGGGAUUCCAGGCAUGAGCCACCAUGGUAGACCCUGCAUUACUCCUCUGUGCUCACUGCCACACGCAGCUCAACCUGAGCUACACAGCCAGGUGUCAGGUGCGUCUCUGCUGAUCUGAGUCUAACUGCAGCAUGGACCUGGGUUUUCCCUGAAGCAUCUCCAGGGCUGGAGGGACGACCGCCAUGCACUGAGGGCUCAUCCAUCCGCAGAGCAGGGCAGUGGGAGGAGACGCCAUGACCCCCAUCCUCACGGUCCUGAUCUGUCUCGGGCUGAGUCUGGGCCCCAGGACCCACGUGCAGGCAGGGCACCUCCCCAAGCCCACCCUCUGGGCUGAGCCAGGCUCUGUGAUCAUCCAGGGAAGUCCUGUGACCCUCAGGUGUCAGGGGAGCCUUCAGGCUGAGGAGUACCAUCUAUAUAGGGAAAACAAAUCAGCAUCCUGGGUUAGACGGAUACAAGAGCCUGGGAAGAAUGGCCAGUUCCCCAUCCCAUCCAUCACCUGGGAACACGCAGGGCGGUAUCACUGUCAGUACUACAGCCACAAUCACUCAUCAGAGUACAGUGACCCCCUGGAGCUGGUGGUGACAGGAGCCUACAGCAAACCCACCCUCUCAGCUCUGCCCAGCCCUGUGGUGACCUUAGGAGGGAACGUGACCCUCCAGUGUGUCUCACAGGUGGCAUUUGACGGCUUCAUUCUGUGUAAGGAAGGAGAAGAUGAACACCCACAACGCCUGAACUCCCAUUCCCAUGCCCGUGGGUGGUCCUGGGCCAUCUUCUCCGUGGGCCCCGUGAGCCCGAGUCGCAGGUGGUCGUACAGGUGCUAUGCUUAUGACUCGAACUCUCCCUAUGUGUGGUCUCUACCCAGUGAUCUCCUGGAGCUCCUGGUCCCAGGUGUUUCUAAGAAGCCAUCACUCUCAGUGCAGCCAGGUCCUAUGGUGGCCCCCGGGGAGAGCCUGACCCUCCAGUGUGUCUCUGAUGUCGGCUACGACAGAUUUGUUCUGUAUAAGGAGGGAGAACGUGACUUCCUCCAGCGCCCUGGUUGGCAGCCCCAGGCUGGGCUCUCCCAGGCCAACUUCACCCUGGGCCCUGUGAGCCCCUCCCACGGGGGCCAGUACAGAUGCUACAGUGCACACAACCUCUCCUCCGAGUGGUCGGCCCCCAGUGACCCCCUGGACAUCCUGAUCACAGGACAGUUCUAUGACAGACCCUCUCUCUCGGUGCAGCCGGUCCCCACAGUAGCCCCAGGAAAGAACGUGACCCUGCUGUGUCAGUCACGGGGGCAGUUCCACACUUUCCUUCUGACCAAGGAGGGGGCAGGCCAUCCCCCACUGCAUCUGAGAUCAGAGCACCAAGCUCAGCAGAACCAGGCUGAAUUCCGCAUGGGUCCUGUGACCUCAGCCCACGUGGGGACCUACAGAUGCUACAGCUCACUCAGCUCCAACCCCUACCUGCUGUCUCUCCCCAGUGACCCCCUGGAGCUCGUGGUCUCAGAGCCCCUGAGUAUAAGCCCUUCACCCACACCUGCGGGGUCCCUGGGCCAUCUCAAGACAAGAGAGGAGGCUGCUUGGGCCUCGGUGGGAUCUGACUGUGAUGAGGCUGGAGUCCACCCCAGAUGUGCUCCUUUAGAGAGAAGCACCCCAGCUGUGGGUGCCGCUCACACUGCCCCUCCUGUGCUCACCUGGAGGCCUCUGUGCUCAGGGCAUCCCUGAGAAUAAGGAGGGGCCCUGCACCUGCUCCCUGGACAAGUCAGCAUCCCUAGGCCAACACCCCCAGGAUUACACAGUGGAGAAUCUCAUCCGCAUGGGUGUGGCUGGCUUGGUCCUGGUGGUCCUCGGGAUUCUGCUAUUUGAGGCUCAGCACAGCCAGAGAAGCCUACAAGAUGCAGCCGGGAGGUGAACAGCAGAGAGGACAAUGCAUCCUUCAGCGUGGUGGAGCCUCAGGGACAGAUCUGAUGAUCCCAGGAGGCUCUGGAGGACAAUCUAGGACCUACAUUAUCUGGACUGUAUGCUGGUCAUUUCUAGAGACAGCAAUCAAUAUUUGAGUGUAAGGAAACUGUCUGGGGUGAUUCCUAGAAGAUCAUUAAACUGUGGUACAUUUUUUUGUCUAUGAAUGUUGACUUCCCUUGACUGGAUCCCCUUUUUUUCCCAUCCCCAGACAUGAGGCUCCAUCCCACAUGGCACCGUUGGGUCCACACCUCCACACACCUGUGUGCUCUGGUCCACGGCAUGUGACACAGUCUUCCUUAUUCCUCAUUGUCACACUCCUUGAUGUCACUUACUGAGUCCCCGUCUCUUCAGUUCAGAGAUCCAAACCUGAACCACCAACUAAAUCAACGACAGGAGAUCAGAUUCCAACCAGGAAAACAUAAAUCCACCCUGCUGCCCUGACACCCUCUCUGUACCUUAUGAGCCCUUCCCUCUUUCUCAGAUGCUAUCUGUGUAAUUUCUCCUGAAAUAUCACCACUUGGAAUCAUCACACUGGCAUUUCAAGUGACACCACAGCUAUGCUGAUUCAGAAAAAGACAUCUCUAAAAUACUGUAAUUAGUGGUAUCUACCAAUUUCUGUGACAUAAAUAUUUUUCUCAUGGCCCAAAUCAAGGUGCCAAUGGGUUCUCACUGAAUACAGGGUUGGGAAGCAAGGGACAGAACUGUCUUCACUAAUGAGCACCAGGGACCUGUGGCACAUCCCACUGAGAGCUCACCCAUAUACCUACAGUCCUUUCUAUUUCAGAGGCAAUGAUCACUUCUACUUCAGUGUUAUGGCACAGGUCAAAUGAAAUUCUGACACUGUUAUCCUAGCAUAUCCACAAAAGACAAACCUAUUAAUAUCUGAUGUGGGAGAUAACACGGCUCACCUAAAAAUCAAAGUACAUGCCGGGCGCGGUGGCUCACGCCUGUAAUCCCAGCACUUUGGGAGGCCAAGGCAGGCAGAUCACGAGGUCAGGAGAUCUAGACCAUCCUGGCUAACAUGGUGAAACCCCGUCUCUACUAAAUACACAAAAAAAUAUUGGCCGGGCGUGGUGGUGGGCGCCUGUAGUCCCAGCUACUCAGGAGGCUGAGGCAGGAGAAUGGCGUGAACCUGGGAGGCGGAGCUUGCAAUGGGCCGAGAUUGCGACACUGCCCUCCAGCCUGGGCGACAGAGCAAGACUCCGUCUCAAAAAAAAAAAAAAAUCCAAGUACAACAUAAGAAAAAUGUUAACAGAACUAUGCAGUUUCGAUGAAAGAAUUUUUUUUGAGAUGGAGUUUUGCUUUGUUGCCCAGGCUGGAGUGCAAUGGUGCAAUCUCGGCUCACUGCAACCUCCACUUCCCAGGUUCAAGCAAUUCUCCUGCCUCUGCCUCCCGAGUUACUGGACUACAGGUGUGCACCACCAUUCCCGGCUAUUUUUUGUAUUUUUAGUAGAGACGGGGGUCUCGCCAUGUUAGUGAGGCUGGUCUUGAACUCCUGACCUCAGGUUAUCCACCUGCCUCAGCCUCCCAGAGUGCUGGGAUUACAGGUGUAAGCCACUGUGCCCGGCUGAUGGAAGAAUUCUUAAAUGACUCGUUCUACUUUCUGCUGGUCCAGGCACUCCUUGGCUUGGGGCAGCAUUCCACCAGUUUCUGCCUCCAUCUUCUCAAUGCUUACACCUACCUGGUUGCCUCUGUCUUCACACCCAUUCUUCUGUGUGUGUCUUUUCUCUUCUUCAGAUUAUGAUAUCACUCAGAUCAGAUUAGGACUCAUCCUAAUUCGUUAUGAUCCCUUGAUCAUAACUUAAAUGCAUUUGCAAAGACUAUUUCCAACUAUGUUCACAUUUAUAGCUAAUGGGGCUCAGGAUUUCAACGUGUAUAUUAGGGGGAACAAGUCAAUUUAUGACAGUGUCUACAAGAAAAGUAUGCAUAGAAAUACAUUUAACCAAAUACAAAAAUUAGGUGGGUGUGGUGGUACACGCCUGUAAUCCCAGCUACUCAGGAGGCUGAGACAGGAGAAUCGCGUCAACCCAGGAAACAGAGGUUGCAGUGAGCUGAGAUCUUGCCAUUGCACUCCAGCCUGGGCAACAGAGUGAGACUCUGUCUCAAAAAAAGAGAAAUACAUUUAACCAAAGAGAUGCAAUACGUAUACAUUGACAAUUUUAAAAUACUGCUCAAAGAAAUAACAAAAGACCUAAAUGAGGAAAAAGUCAUCCCAGUAUCAUAAAUCAAAAGGCUUAAAAUUAGUUAUCUCCCUCUAGGGAACCUAGACUAAUACACUCACCCCGUCUCCUUGUUCGGAGGCUCUCCUGCCUAUCAGCUGUUCUCCUCUGUGCUUUCCAUGUCCCUGUGGUUCUCUGGUGAGCCCCAUCAUGCUGUCCUAGAAGAUCCACUUAGAAUUUCGGUAUUUACUCACCAUUUUGACUCCUCUUAACGAGACAGGCACAUGCCAGCUGUUUCCAUUCAUCCAACCUGAACCUGAGCCCCCGAUCAUUUUUUCUACCACUUUUCAGUCCUGGGAAACUCAGUCCCAAUGUGCUUGUCAUUCAUUUGAGAAUAAUUUUCAUUUUCUCCAGUAGUUUUAAAAUUACUUUGUAUCUAUUCUAGAUAUCGUUUGCUCUAUCAUAGUUAAGACAUUAAUGUUAUUUAUGAAUUUGUGCACAUUAAACUCAUGAUCUUUCAUUUCUGUAAAAAUGUCAACUAUUUCCUUUGCAAGUAUUUAUUGACUAACAUACUCCUUAUUUCCUUCAUUCUGAAAGUGUGACACAUAGAGAUAUAUCUGUUUCCUCUUCUCACUCUAUUCUUUGUGUGCAUUAAUUAUCUUUUCUAUUUUUUUCAUUUCUAGUUUUUCUCCGAUGACUAAUGAAAAAUUUAAUAAAUAUUCUACACCAA